GGGAGUCCGCGCGUGCCCGCGCCGAGCUGCCUGCUCCGGCGGCUUCGCUGCUAGCUCGCGGCGACGUCGGGCCGAUUUUCCCAGGAUGACAGAGCUGAGGCAGAGGGUGGCCCAUGAGCCGGUUGCGCCACCCGAGGACAAGGAGUCAGAGUCAGAAGCAAAGGUAGAUGGAGAGACUGCAUCGGACAGUGAGAGCCGGGCAGAAUCCGCACCCCUGCCAGUCUCUGCAGAUGAUACCCCGGAGGUCCUCAAUAGGGCCCUUUCCAACUUGUCUUCAAGAUGGAAGAACUGGUGGGUGAGAGGCAUCCUGACUUUGGCCAUGAUUGCAUUUUUCUUCAUCAUCAUUUACCUGGGACCAAUGGUUUUGAUGAUAAUCGUGAUGUGCGUUCAGAUUAAGUGUUUCCAUGAGAUAAUCACUAUUGGCUACAACGUCUACCACUCAUAUGAUCUGCCCUGGUUCAGGACGCUCAGCUGGUACUUUCUCCUGUGUGUAAACUAUUUCUUCUAUGGUGAGACAGUGACGGAUUACUUCUUCACCCUGGUCCAGAGAGAAGAGCCUUUGCGGAUUCUCAGUAAAUACCACCGGUUCAUUUCCUUUACUCUCUAUCUAAUAGGAUUCUGCAUGUUUGUACUGAGUCUGGUCAAGAAGCAUUAUCGACUGCAGUUCUACAUGUUUGGCUGGACCCAUGUGACAUUGCUGAUUGUUGUAACACAGUCACAUCUUGUUAUCCACAACCUAUUUGAAGGAAUGAUCUGGUUCAUUGUCCCCAUAUCUUGUGUGAUCUGUAAUGACAUCAUGGCCUAUAUGUUUGGCUUUUUCUUUGGUCGGACCCCACUCAUCAAGCUGUCCCCGAAGAAGACCUGGGAAGGCUUCAUUGGGGGCUUCUUUGCUACUGUGGUGUUUGGCCUUCUGCUGUCCUAUGUGAUGUCCGGGUACAGAUGCUUUGUCUGCCCUGUGGAGUACAACAAUGACACCAACAGCUUCACUGUGGACUGUGAGCCCUCGGACCUGUUUCGCCUGCAGGAGUACAACAUUCCUGGGGUGAUCCAGUCAGUCAUUGGCUGGAAAACGGUCCGGAUGUACCCCUUCCAGAUUCACAGCAUCGCUCUCUCCACCUUUGCCUCGCUCAUUGGCCCCUUUGGAGGAUUCUUCGCAAGUGGAUUCAAACGAGCCUUUAAAAUCAAAGACUUUGCCAAUACCAUUCCUGGCCAUGGAGGCAUCAUGGAUCGCUUUGACUGCCAGUAUCUGAUGGCCACCUUUGUCAAUGUAUACAUCGCCAGUUUUAUCAGAGGCCCUAACCCAAGCAAACUGAUUCAGCAGUUCCUGACUUUACGGCCAGAUCAGCAGCUCCACAUCUUCAACACGCUGCGGUCUCAUCUGAUCGACAAAGGGAUGCUGACAUCCACCACAGAGGACGAGUAGGGGCCACCCAGGGCCAGGAGAACAGGAACAGAACUGAGCAGGGGCAGGUCUCCAAGGCAAGCCCAGCUGGUGUGACUUAGACAAUGACGAGGCUUCAACUCACUGUCUUUUUUUUUUUUUUUUGGAGGGUAUUUUUUAUUUGUGGGUUCAAAAAAUCUGUAUAUACAGUCUAUGUGUUUAGAAUUUGUGUUGUAAGUAAACUACAGCUUUGAGUUGGAAAGAAGUCACGGGUUGUAAAACCAUUUGGAUUUUUUUAAAACAAAAGUAUUAAUAAUCUGGAAGACAGUGUUGCCCAGGUCAGGAGUGUUUUCUUGGUGGUUCCAGCCCCCAUCAAUUGAACUGUUUCUGGGCUCAGUCAGACACAGACAUUCAUCUGUGUCUGACCAAAUCAGGGGACUUCCCCACCUGUGGUGGGAGGCACAGCUUAGAUGUUUUGUACACCUGGUCUUUUCUAGAAAUCCCUGCUUGGAGCUGCAGAAGGGUUGCCUUCUGUAGGUCGGAGGAAUGGAGGCUUACUAACCAGGUAAGCCUUCUAUGCAUCCACACCAAAAUCCUGCAGAAUGUAAGUAAGCUCUGCUUUAUAAGAUGGGUUCACCUUCAUCGCAGACUGAAAGUUUCAGUUUUUAUUUUUUUCAGAAAGCACGAAAAAUUAUUUAUAAUAGUCUGGAGAAAAAACACACUGUAAUAUUUCAAGUGUAUGCAGUAGAAUGUACUGUAACUGAGCCCUUUCCCACAUGUCUAGGCUCCAAUGUCUCCUGUAGGUCCACCUAACUGUGUGUUUUCAGGGACAAUGCCAUCCAUGUUUGUGCUGUAGACUUGCUGCUGCUGAAUCCUUUCUGGGGACUUUCUCAUCGGGCAGGGAGCAGAGGGCUUCUCGUUCAUGCACCCUUUGCCUGAACACCCAUGUAGCUGCUGUGUUGUGUAUAUAUUACUCUUAAGAGGAGUGUGUGUGUCUGUGUUUGUUUUAAAAGUCACUUAUUUCUUACAGUGAUUUCAAUUGCACCAUGACUUCUUCACUAAAACCACAAAGUCCUGCUUAAAACUAUGGAAAACCUAACCUGAUUAGAGCCUUGACUAUUUUGAAGAUUAAAUGCACACUUUUUAUAUAAUGUGACCAGUUUAAAUGUAGUUUGUAUUGUACUGGGGGACCUUUCGUUGUUGUUGUUUGCUUAAACUGUGAUUUUUUUUCCCCUCCCUAAUUUCAGGGGUGAGAUUGACUUUGGGAAGACAGAUUAGUUCUUUGUCAGGCCAACAAGUGAUGGAGUGCGGGAGAGAGAACUUGGCACCCAAAUAUAUCAAACUAUUCCGUGCCGUGGAUGUUUUCAUUGCCAACGAGGGUGUAAUGAUUUGCUUCUGCACCUUGGUCUAGUGCUGGUUUGUGGUGUUUUUGUUUGUAAAUUAGCCUCACUGCCUCCCUGAAAGUGCACAGUCAGCCCAGGUCUCUAGAGUGUCCAGCAGAGGAUGGAGCCCUCGGGAUGUUUCAGCUCACACAUCCUUGAGUGACUUCCCAUAUGUGUGUGGGGCUGAAGCGGCUUCUUUCCGCUGAACUUUUAUUUCCAUUUCAGCCUCGUGGCUUCUCUUAUUCAGGUCCAAGGCCCCUUAAAAACAAAACAUAUUAUCGCAAGGGCUUUCAUUUCAGUAUUGGCUGUGUCACUGGCAGGAUGCAUCACUCUCCAGGGCCUCUUUUUCGGAGCUACUCCCAAUUCCACUCUUCUGUGAUUCUGGCUGAGCAAGUUCAUGCCGGUAGAGGCUCAUUAAGUGAGGUCCUGGGCACCCCCCAAACAGGAAGUGUUUUCAGGCCCUUACAUGCUUAUCCUUAAGGUGAGUAGGUAUCUCAGCAGCACACCCGAACAGUAAAGGUGAUCAAUAACGAAACUGUAGUUUUCAGAUUGAAGAAUGAACCUGGAUCACCAAACUAGAUACCGAAAGGGCUCCUCAUUUGUCUCUUUUGUCCCAUUGUGGGCAUAUGGUGGGCUCCUUGAGAGGAGGGAGUCUCAGCUGGGGCCUGGCUGCAGAGACCUGCUCUUGAAUAGGGCUGCCUUUGGGAUCAGGGAGCCGAGCAUACUGGGCAAGGCUCAUCAUGUUCCUUUGUGGAAGUGGUUACUUGGUGGGGGUGGGGUGGGGAAGGGGGGUCUAGGAAGCCGAAGCUGAGUGCGCACUAGAGCUGCUAGCAGGCAGGCCAGAGGGUCAGCUUGUGUUUUAUUUUCUGAUUUCUCCUGCAUGCUUUCUGGAGAUGAGGAUUUUUUGUCAGGUAGCUAGGAGAGCACUGCCACCUUGUGUCCAUAUAGCACAAUGUUUCUCUUUCCUAUUCACAGACAAGAUUCAAGAAACCAUUUUUACGUGUGUACAUUCAAAUCUUCAUGAAUGGCAUCACUUGCUUUAGACCCAUUUUUUUUUUAUUGGUCAGAAAUAAAAUGUGACUGCAACUGUGUGCCCUCCCUUGUCGUGAAUUCCCUGUUUAUCACUUCCAUGCAUGGUUUUAUGCUUCUCAUUUGUUUAUGUAUUCAUGAAUACUGCAUAGUCCUGAUUCAGAGACUUUUGCUUUGCUUUCCAACUUGUAUCCCUACAUUCUCACAACAGCCUUCUUACCUCGGGUGAGAGUCAUGAGCACCUUACCAGGCAGGGAGCUUCCCCAGGAUAGUGUGGUGGAGUCAGGACUCACUCCAUCCUGCACUUUACCCACAGGACACCUGGAGGGUCCCCCAGCCCUGCUUGCUUUUGUGAACGUCGUGUGAGUACACCGAGGUGUUGCAGCUUUCCUUCCCUCUAGCUCAGGAGGCCUGGCCUGAGCCAGGUUGGAGCUUAAAUUGCUGUUGGCUCCUGCCUGGUGGAACAAGGGGGUCAUAGAAACCAGGGCUGAUGGGCACCCCCCAGCCCCUGGGAGCUCUGCUCAUGACCGCUCACAGGGUACCGAGUCUUUGCCUUUUGUGUGUGCGCAUGCUGCCCUCUUAACUGCUUUUAGUAUUCAGAAAGGUUCCAUUUAUGUUUUACUCCUGAAAGUGAAACCCUCUUAGGCAACUUGUUUCAUAUUCUGGGCAUUUUAGUAGCUACAGUAUUUUGCAUUUAAAAUGUAAUUACUCUUAGUAUUGUACAGCCCUAUAAUGUAUGAGAACUAGUUUCACAUCCUUUGAAACUAAUCUCUUUCAUUGGGGAGGAUACAACUUUUGACUUUACACAGGUGGACUUUGAAUCCAUUUUUAUAGAAUUUUUUUCCACUGUAACUUGACCUAUAUUAUGCAAGAAAAUCCCAAAAAUAUGUUUUAAGGGAGACUACACAGACCUUGUGAUUUGGUCUGAGCUAGUUGCUGAGUUGACUGGAGCCUUAUUUGAAUGGAUCUUUGAGUUGAGAUCUUCACACUGUCAGUGAGCCCUUGGCUCAGCCCUUGUCACCUGUUUGUAUGGGGACCAUGUUUCCCAAAGCUCAGGUUCAUCUCCACUAUUGACAGAGUCGGGUAGUGGGAGAGUAUAAGUGACUUGAGACAGAGUGUCCUUGCUCAGAAAACUGUGAAGCAGGGGUCUUGUUAGUUACAAAGCCAGUCCUAGUUGCAUGUCCAAGGGGGUAGAUUUUCAUCACCCUACUAAAUGUGGUAUGUCACUGCUGAAGCCUUUUCCUGUUUUAGUAAUAUCUUAGGCACUAUUGUCUUUUGUCUUCCAGAGUAACAUAUCUGGGCCCACCUUUCUUGCACACUGUGAUUAUGUGCUAAGAAAAGGGUGGAGUUGGGAGGACAAUUUCACUUGAACAGGUUUCUGUUCUUCUGAGGUCAGGGUGGGGAGGAUGUCCAGGUGACUUUUAUGGACACAUUGCAAGACAGUAAGCCGCGGAUGGACUCUCACUUGUGCUUUGGAACACUGGACUCCAAAGAGCAGGUGGAACAAACUCUGGCCUGAAGAUGAUGGCUAAUACUCAGGCAGAGCCCCGUAUUCUUCCCUGACUUGGUCAAAACAAACUUCCUUUUCCCUUGAUCACCCUGCACGCAGCUGCCCAGCUUCCAGUUUUUAAAGAGAUGAACAGCUCUCACUUCCUGACUCAGUUUCUCUUGUUGGGUGGGGGCCUUGUGCCACAACCUGCAUGGGGUGCUAGGGUUUAAACCAAGUGGUCACGAAGGAUUCUUAUCUCAGGGCUCUGCCUGGCCCACCUUCUCUUGGGCCUGGACUCUCCUUAUCCACAUCCCUGCAGAAGGUGGGCCCUAUUCUCAGAAGAGUCCUGGCUGCUGUUGCCAUCUGAAUGCGCCCUUCCCUUUCAGGUUGACCAGCAGUGGCCUUACCUGGCCUCUCAGGUGGAUGGAGGCUGUUCUCAUCUGGGGCUGUCUCUUGAUUAAGGCUGUCACCUGUUUGUAUAGGGACCAUGUUUCCCAACGCACUUUGAGUGCAGUUUAGGAGGUAUCCUUUGGAUGCUGAAGUGUUGGGAUUUUGAGGACAUGCGGAUGAUUUAUGAGAAUAGAGGGGCAGAGUUUGUGAAGUCUAGGGUUUUUUGUCCAGUGGGUUUCAAAUUUGUUGGCUGUUUAAAGACCCUGUCUCCUCCCCCACCCUCCCCUUCCUUUUCCCAUCAAAUGCCUACCUACUGAGGCGCCUUCUCUUUUUAUUCUUGAGCCAAUGAGAUAUCAGUGUGUUUAUUAAUAAGGAUUGCAAUAGUAUAGUGCUUAAUAUGUGCCAGGCAUAGUGCUAAGGGUUUACAUACGUUAUCCCUUUUAAUCCAGAAAACAGCCUUUGAUUAGGUAUUGUUGUCUCCAUUUUAUAGAUGAGGAAACUGAGGCAGUAUGACUGAGGCCGAGAGCAGUGGUUAAGACAGACUUUGGGAUCAAAUCACCCUAGGUGCGGGCAGGUUUCUAGGCUGCUCUAAGCUUCUACCUUGAAGGCAGUUGGGUCUGAUAAUAGUACCUUCUUCCUGGGGUGGUUGUGAGGAUAUAACGAGGUAAUGCAUGUAAGCAUUUAGUACCAUGCCUGGCACAUAGUAAGCACUCAAUAAAUGGUAGUUACUUUUGUUGAGCUCAGCUGGUAGUUUGACCUCCGUUGGUGCAAUGCCAGAGAUGGGAUUGUCAGCCACCACACUGCCACCACCCUGCACACAGUCUGGGUCCCUCCGAGAGAAGCACGCCAACCUUAACAUCCCCUACAGCAUCUUGGUGCUUCACACACCAUUUAGGAGGCCACCCUAACGAGGCAAGAGGACAUGGGGGUGUGCAGAAGUUCUGUUCUUAGUGAGAAUGGCUGGCCUGAGAAUCCAGCUCACCUCCUCUGCCCACAGUCUGGACUGCUUGUGGGAAGGCCAUCUCCUCCUGUCUGGUGGUACCUCCACUCUGGGCAGGGAGGGCCUGUCUGUGACUCGCUCUGGACCCCACUUCCCGCUCUGGCCAAGGGCUGUCUUCUGUGCACAUAGCUCAGGAGCCUGCAGCAGUUCCCUGUAUGGGUGGAUGUCCUCAGGGGCCAAGAAGAGAAGAAUGGGGACAACAGAAACCUGCUUUGUAGGGGAUUAUGUAGACUAAAAGCCUAGAAGUUCUGCCCACAUCCUUAUGACGCAGCCAAUCUGGAGCUUCAUGUUUCCUUCUAAAAGUAGUAACCGGGUAGAAGUGGGUGACCCAUUGAGGACACAUGAUGUGAGGUAUUUCUGCCGGAUUCUAGGUUAGCAAAGACUCAAAUGGGUGACUCAUGAAUGAAGGGAGAACAGGCACAGGACUUAAUGAAAAGAGUUUCUUGAACUUAGUUUUCUGAAUGGGGGUGGGGAGUUGGGGCACGUGUGUGUAAGGGGAGGCUGCCUCACUUUGAAGGAAUGGUGUUGGCUAACAGGAUCCAUGAAAUUCCUAGGUCAGUUGAAUAAUAACUGAACUACUGGUUUGACUGUGGAUUAUUUCCUGGGUAUUAGUGGGACCCAACAGCACAUUGCUAUUAAUAGUAUGGAAAUAAUGGUCCCUCUGUUUCAUUGAAUUGCUGAAGUAAUGAUAAUGCCAUGAACCAGGAGAAGAUGGUUGUGGGGGUUUCUAGGAAGCAGCUGCUGUGACAGGCCAAUCCCAGGCUUGCCCCCGAGCCCUCCUGUCCUUCUGGGUUUGUGUUUGCCUUGCCUGGUGCUUCCUCCCUCAUUGUGUUGUUGAAUAGACCUAGGCAGCCUUGUAUCCAUAGAAAGCCUCCACUGCUGGGCCGGGGAGGGGGUUGUGGUAAGGGCCCUCUGGAAAUCAAGCAGAGAAUGCCUUUGCAGUGGUCUCCCGGGCAUUGGGCAGGGCCUAGCCUUUUGCAGCCCCCAGAGGACCUUGCCUGCAUAAAGCACUCAGAAGGGUUAGCCACCUGGUGAUUUUGUCUCUAGUGAAACUGUGUUUGCCGAUAAUCAUCCACAUAGCCACCUCUGUCCUCGCAGUUUGGAUGCCUUUUUUUGACACCUGCGCUAGGUUCUUGUAUGCUGGCUUUUCUUAAAGGAACAGCAGAGUAGAAAAGAGGUUGAGAAUGUUUUCUAGCAGGCAGAAUGUGCAUACAUGUUUUCAUGAGUGUCCUUUGGGUGCUGUUUCUUUUAAAUCCUCUGUGCACAGGGCUCUGGCCUUUAGUAAACUGUUUUUCUGUCUUACGUCAUGCUGACUGGGUGCUAGGGGCUGAUUACAAAGGGGAAGAGUUGAACAGACAUCAGGGGCCGAUGAAACCAAAGGACUAGGAGUCAGGAGAACAAGUCAGGGAUUAGGAGACAGCGGUUUGGUUUAUUGUUAUCCAGCUGGAGGACUCCUAGGGGCAGCAGCAGGAGGAAUACCAGGGCCACGGAGGGGCCAGGAGUCUCACAGUGGAGGGCAGACUCUAACAGAUGCCAGCUGAACGCUCGCUGGCCCUGGAUGUCAUACGAGUUGGGGACCAGAAAUCUGGGCUCAGAGAACCCGUCCAGGGAGAUUUGAAGCCAUGGGUUAUCUUCUAGAGUUGAUACUGAUAAUAUAUUUUAAUUUUUAUUGAUGUUUAAUACCUUCUGAAACAGGAGGGUAAGAUCAGAUGGGAAGCCCCUCUGUUGAAGGAUCUUGGGAACCUUGGUGGUUUUUUUUUUUUUUUUGGUUUUUUUUUUUUGAUCGAGCUGUGGACAUCCUUCUUAAUUCGAUUCUGAGGAUUUGUUUAACUAAAAAGUUCCCAAACACAGAAAGGGCCUCCCCACCUGCUUUGGGGAGCUGUCUGUGCUGGGAGUGCCAGGCAUCCCAUGGGACCCAUCACUGCCAGUGUCUGUGCCUCCCAGAGGUCAGCCGUGUCUGCCCUGGCUCUGUCUCCUCUGUGACAGGGCAGAGCAUUUCUGGUCAGUUUCUCCAUGGUGCCUCCCACCCCUUUGUAAAGUGGAUGGACAUGAUGGAAUUCAGUUGUCUCACCCUGAUAGCCUGGGUGUUGAUAUUCACUUUACCCGCACUCAGACACAGGCGACCUUGAAGCAGUUCUCGGUGUGUAGAGUCCACGUGACAGUCCCCACAGCCUCCCCAGAUAGCUGUGUGCCUGUGCGCUACUGCUGUGCCAUUUUCCCAACUUGGCGUUUCACUAAAUGCAGCUGAUCUCUCUCUCUGUGCACUCGUGAUCCAUGUUGAACAAUACAUGUAGGUUCUUUUUCCACGCAAUGUAAGAACAUGAUAUACUGUACGUUGGAAAGCAUUUACCUUAUUUAUAUACCUGAAUGUUCCUACUACACAAAUAAACAUAUAUUAAAUUCUA